CUCCUCCUCCUCCUCCUGCUCCUCCUCCUCCUGCUCCUCCUCCUCCUCCUCCUCCUCCUCCUCCUUCUCCUCCUCCUCCCGGUCUGAGGGCGGCGGUCUCCGACUCAAGACCCUGGGGCUCCGGGUCUUCUUAGCAGCCGCCGCAGCAGCCGCGGCGACGUCACUGUCCUCUCGGCCUGGCACACAGCGCUCCGGCCGCCGAAUGCCCGUGGACGCGCAUCUCUUCCCAGAGUUCCUGCUUCCUGGGCCAGCCAAAGCCGCAGAGAACGCCUCAGGGUCUUGCCUGCUGUGAGUGCCUUGAAGAGGGAGCAGCGGGCACGAUCAAAGAGACACCUGGCUCAAGGACCAAUAAGGAGUAUGGCUGCCCCUCCCAAAGCUCCCAUCCGUGUCAGGAAUUUGACCAUCAGAGCAGGAGCCCUCACUGGGAAGGAGAACAACAUGCUGCAGCCCGAGACCCACAUCUUCACAGCCCCCGAGGAGGGGAGCUCCCAAGGGGCUCUGCUGCUUGGCCAGGCCCCAGAACCUUUGUCUCUGCCCUGUACUCCAGUGACCUUGGAGCAGCAACUGGUUUCUCCUUCUGGGGAUCCCCACAGGGCCCCUGCCCUGCCCAGCAUAUGCUCAACUCUGAUCCUCCAGCCCUGUGCCACCCUUGACCCUCUUCUACUGCAGCCACAGGUCCCCAAAGUCUCUGACCAGGCUUUGGUUUCUGCCCACUCAGAGUGGCAGCGGAAGCUGGAGGCCGCUGAGGCUCUGCUGACUCUGAGAAACUCUGCCCAGGCCCCUCCUGACUCCAUCUCCCUGCACCAGCCUUGCAACCCACCAGCUCCUGCUGGAGAUAAAGGAUUCCAGCCUCCCAGCCCCUCUCUCCGCCCCAGGCCAGCCAGCUCCAUCUCGCUGCCUAUUGGACAUCUGGGAUGCAUCUCCCUCUUGAGCUAGGAACCCAGAGGAGGAGGCCUCAAUAGAGCACUGCCUAUUUGGUAUCCAGUUUCUGAAUGUGCAAAAUGGUUAACGUCCAAAACGCUUAACGUCUUUUUUUAAAGCCUUCAGGUGUUUUAUAAGCUUUUUAUUAUAUGGGGCAACUCCUUGGCUGAGGGUGGAUAUUCUUGUACCUCUGUCCCUUACUCUUUUGGAUGCUGGGGCCUUUUUCUGUCUCAUAAAGACAGGAUUGUGCAAUCUAAGUUGAUCAGUCUCUCAGUGGGGUUCUGUGUGAGUUCAUAUGCCAGAGUUUUUAUUCGUCUUGUGAUUGCUGACAUACCUGUGCACUCAUGUGUAUACCCCUGCAUGUGGAAACAUGAAGAUGUUUUCACUUUGUGUCUAGGUUUAUGUACGUGAACAAAUAAUAAACCGUUGUUGUUAUAAGGCA